AGACGACGCGCCGUGCGCCUGCGCACGGCUUGCCCAUGUGUGCUGCAGCCGUCAGCCGGCCCAGCUGAGCAGCAGCAACGGACCUUGUUAACGGCGCGGCAGCCUCCACCGCCUGCUGUUGCCCUCCUCUCUCGGUGGUCUGUCCGCCCAGCGCACGUCACCAUGGGCAAGAGCCGGACGAAGCGCUUCAAGCGACCUCAGUUCUCCCCUACGGGCGACUGUCAGGCCGAGGCGGCUGCGGCGGCGAAUGGGACCGGAGGCGAGGAGGACGACGGGCCGGCGGCGGAGCUGCUGGAAAAGCUCCAGCACCCGAGCGCCGAGGUCCGCGAGUGCGCCUGCGCAGGGCUGGCCCGGCUGGUGCAGCAGCGGCCGGCACUCCCGGGCCUGGCGCGACGAGACGCCGUGCGCCGCCUCGGGCCGCUGCUGCUAGACCCCAGCCUGGCCGUCAGGGAGACUGCAGCCGGCGCGCUGAGGCACUGGCCCGGUCUCCCGUUUGCAGAGAUUUGAAGCCAGUCUCCAGGCUCCGGAGAAGCCCAGUAUCCCCGCAUCUCAUCUGUCCACCUGGCUGCUUCACCUGCAGCGUCCACCUGCUCAGGCGUCCUGCCCUCACGCCUUGCGCACGUUUUACACUCUCCAAAAGCCCUCCUUAGGGUCCCUUGCUUGGAUGAACUCUUCAGUUCAUGUGUCAGGAAUCGUUCUAGAUGCAGGGGACUUUGAGCAGCCAAGACUUUUGAGCGAGAUCUGUUGACAGCCAAGAUCCCUGUCUUGGCACAAGUCAUGUUGAUGGGGAGACAGACAGGAAGCUAGUAAAAAGAAAUCUCAGUGCUUGUGGAGGUUUUGAAGUUUGUGAUGACAUGGUGACUAAGGAUAUCAUGACCCCUCUGGUUGCGCUGCUAAAAGAGUGUAGUGCUGGACUGGAUUCAAAUGAGAUGUCUCUGCAGGAGAAAAAAGAUCAGAACAGAAAUUCUAUUGAGAACAUAGCCAAUGAGACUGUGAACGUGCUGUGGAAUAUAUGUGAAUGCAGUAGUAGAGCAGUGUCUAUAUUCAACAAAGAAGGGUGUUUGGAGAUUGUGUUAAAGUAUUUAAGUAGGUUUCCUACCAAUGUUGACCUGGCUAUUUCAGUAGCAUAUUGUUUGCAGACAGUGACUGAGGAUAACCCAGAGCUGCUGAAGUCUUUCAGUGCUACAGCAUUGAACAUGCUGGAAUCAGCACUGCUUUCUCCUGUCAGUUCCAUGGAAUCUCUUCUAUUGAAGACAUUGGUAGCAGGCACAAUUUGGAAUCUAAAGGACAUUAUUCCAUGCAAGAGUCAAGCAGAAAUCAUAAAUGCCUUACUAAAGAUCUUAUCUGAAGUUUUGGGAAUGGAUGCUGGUGAAAUGGUUAUUCAAAUGAAAGAGGCUGAAACGCAAAGGUUAAAAACUGCUGCAGAGGCUGAGGAAAUAUUAGAGAACACUAAUGGGGAUGAUUUGAUUGAAGAUGAUGAAAUGGAAGGAAUUUCUCAUAAAAGAAGAGUCAGAAGGAAAACUUUCGUUUCAGAUUUACUUCCGCCCACUGACAAGGAACUGAGAGAGACUAUAGCAUUGCUGACAGCCCAACAGACUGCUCUGGAAAUUAUUGUCAACAUGUGCUGCAAUGAAGAUCCCUCUGAUGACGAAUGGGAAGAGCUUUCUAGCAGUGAUGAAAGUGACGCAUUUAUGGAGAAUUCCUUCAGUGAGUGCGGGGGACAGCUGUUUUCUCCCCUCUGCCUCUCCCAUGAAGUUCACACGGCUCUCACCAACUACCUCAUCCCAAAGAAGAUUUUUGAGAAAACUGCCUUUCCAAACAGCAUUGCAGUUGACCUAUGUUCUAGGAACCCUACUUGGAAACCUUUGAUUAGAAAAAUGAACACUAUUCAGUGCAGAGCCCUCUUCUGUCUCCAGAGUCUUGUGUCCCUCCUGGAUGUGGAGCACCUGGGAGGAGCCGCAGCCCUUCAGACGCUUGCACAGCAUCUGUCACAGCUGCUUUUUUCUCAACCAGAUUUUGCUAAACAUGUUGACUUUCUAGAAGCCAUAAGUAGUGCUUUGAGGGCCCUUUUGCAAACAAUGGCCUCCAAGAACAUUUCCCAGUGCAUGACUCCUGAUCAGCUGAUGACAUUAUGCAAAGCAGGCAUUCAUAGUAGUAAUGUCGGGGUUAGAGUGAAUGUCGUUAGCAUUUUAGGAAUCACUGGCAGCGUCCUUGCCAAAGAAGAUGGUACACUUGAAACUCUUAAGAACAUUGGGUGCUUUCUGCUUGAAGUUACCACCAAAGAUCCUUCCCUUGUGGUAGCAGGAGAAGCUUUGGAUGCCCUCUUUGAUGUUUUUGCAGAUGGUAAAGAAGCCGAAAGAGCCUCGAUUCAAAUUAAAUUAUUAUCUGCUCUGAAAGAAUUCCAGCCGGUCUUUAAAAUGAAGAUACGUAAAGAAGGGAGAGGUAACUAUAGCACAGAUCAGCUGUGUGUUCUUGACAAUGUGAAAAUGAAUUUGCGAAGAUUUAUUGCUUAUCAAGAAACUGUUGAGAAAAGACUGACUUCUUAAACAAUCCAAAAAAGAAACCAGUUCUUCCCCCAAAGUAUUCAAUGCUUAGAAUACUAAAAGGUUUUCUUUGAAUGUAUAUGUUUCUGAAAGUCAUUUUUUAAUGAUUACAUUCUGUACAUUCUGUAAAAACUUCAAAACCUGGCCAGGCAUGGUGGCUCACGCCUAUAAUCCCAGCACCUUGGGAGACCGAGGCGGGUGGAUCACUUGAGGUCAGGAGUUUGAGGCCAGCCUGGCCAACAUGGUGAAACCGCAUGCAUAAGCAUGGUGGCACAUGCCUGUGAUCCCAGCUACUCGGGAGGCUGAGGGAGGAGAGUCGGUUGAACCUGGGAGACAGAGGUUGCAGUGAGCUGAGAUCACGCUACUGCACUCCAGCCUGGGUGACAGAGGGAGACCCUGUCUCCAAAAAAAAAAAAAAAAAAAAACUUCAAAACCUGUCAGAAACUCUGUUGCUGGUUUUUUUGUGUGUGUGUUUUGUUUGUUUGUUUUGUUUUGUUGUUUUUUUCUUUUUUGAGAUGGAGUCUCACUGCUGCCCAGGCUGUAUUACAGUGCUGCGAUCUUGGCUUACUGCAACCUCUGCCAUUCCAGGUUCAAGCGAUUCUCAUGCCUCAGCCUCCUGAGUAGCUGGAAUUACAGGCACCCACCACCACACCUUGUUUUUGUUUUUGGUUUUUUGGUUUGUUUUUUUUUUUCAGUAGAGACGGGUUUCACCGUGUUGGCCAGGCUGGUCUCAAAUUCCUGACCUCAAGUGAUCCGCCUGCCCUGGCCUCCCAAAGUGCUGGGAUUACAGGCAUGAGCCACCGUGCCUGGCCAGAAACUCUUUUUUAAGUGAUGAGAUCUGUGUGGCAUUUCUAGCGCUCUCUAAAUUAUGUCUCUGGCAUAUUUUAAUCACUGGAAACUCAAAGAGUGGAAGAGUGGAAGUGCGAAGGAAUCUCAGGUAGCUCUUAACUAAUUCGCCAGCAGUGAAGAAACUUCAACCAAUCAUGUUUUCCUUGAAUUUUGCAAAGAAAGAAAAUCCAAAGCAUUGCUUGGAUGUUCUUUUAAGGCAUUUUAUAUCAGUUGAACCUUAAACUGAAAUAUGAAGACAAGCUUUAUAAACUAGUUUUUUGAUAUGAAGUAUAUCAAUUAUGUUUGCCUUUUGUGAAGAAGUAAAUGAGUUGAAUUUCUAUUUCACUUACUAGAUUAUACUAAUGAGCUAAUGGGGUCAUUGCCAUCCUCCCUACUCAUGACUUUGAUGAGUUAUUGCUGUAACAUCACUUCUUGAUUUAAUUUGAUAUGGAAUCAGAAUUGGGAGAAGGUAUUUUUAAAUAAACAACUUUUUAAUGGAAAGUUUUGUGUCUUACAAAAUCUUUUUUAAGAUACCAAAUAAAGGGUUAUUAGUAGAAAAUGAGAUGAUACUAUUCGUGGAUAUUUGUUUGCUAAUGCAUAUUGCUUGGAAUAUAUGUGAGACAUUAAAAAAAUGACAGCACGACUUUGCAGCAUUACCUCUCAGUGUCUUCGAAGUACUAGGUGACAGCUGGGGCUCGAGGGAGUUUCCCUGUGCAUCAUUGUCUCGGCUGGGCCUCUGAACCGGCUUCAUUGUCCAUCCGUUUGCCUGAUGAGAAGGGAAAUUUGAAAAUUUCUGUACAGUUGAUCUCAGUUGCCCUGACAAAAGGCCCAAUCCCCAGUACAGGACUUAAUUUUAAUUCACUGCUUCCACAGCAGCACAAAAUGAGCUAGUAGUGUUAGAUUUCAUCUGCACUGUGAUGUAUUUUACAGUUUUCACCUAUAUGAUAUAGACUGUUGGGAAACCAAGAUUGUUUCCCAGCCCUAAGAGUUCCUAGCCCAUGGCACCAAGUAAAAUAACCCAAAUUGUGUAUAUGGUGGGAAAACAGAAAUGUAUACCAUAUACAACACCUCGCUUUAUUAUGGUCCUUGCUCAUGAAUUUUAAGGUAUAUAUGUAUGUUUAGUGAUCAUUUCAGCUAAAUGAUUGGCCCAAGCAUGUCUCCUUGGAGAACGACUCUUCCAAAAAAGAAAGUAUUAGAGUUCUCUCUGCCUCAAUUAUUUAUAAAAUAUAAUUAUUUUCAAGGAGAAAAAAGUUCCUCAUUCUGUUUAUUCUUCCCCACAGUUUCUGACCUAUAAACAAUAUCCAGGAUAUUUAGCACAGGACCUAGUAUAUAGUCGACUCUUCAUAAAUAUUUGUUGAGUAAAUAAAUGCUGGUGAUUUUCUCGUU